GCCUUUGUCUCUCGCUGCAGCUGGAGCGCUUGGUCUCGUCUUCCCUGCUUUGUGUCCCCUGCUCUUAGAGGCCCAGCCUCUGUGGCCCUCUGACCUGCAAGCAUUGGGAGAUCCACAGCUAAGACGCCAGGGCCUCCCCUGGAAGCCUAGAAAUGACGGAGUCUCGCUCUGUCACCCAGGCUGGAGUGCAAUGGCGUGAUCUUGGCUCACUGCAACCUCUGCCUUCUGGGUUCAAGUGAUUCUCCUGCCUCAGCCUCCCAAGUAGCUGGGAUUACAGGGACCAUUGACAUUUAUGGAUGUGGCCAUAGAAUUCUCUGUGGAGGAGUGGCAAUGCCUGGACACUGCACAGCAGAAUUUAUAUAGGAACGUGAUGUUAGAGAACUACAGAAACCUGGUCUUCCUGGGUAUUGCUGUCUCUAAGCCAGACCUGAUCACCUGUCUGGAGCAAGGCAAAGAGCCCUGGAAUAUGGAGAGACAUGAGAUGGUGGCCAAACCCCCAGGUAUGUGUUGUUAUUUUGCCCAAGACCUUCGGCCAGAGCAGAGCAUAAAAGCUUCUUUGCAAAGAAUAAUACUGAGAAAAUAUGAAAAAUGUGGACAUCACAAUUUACAGUUAAAAAAAGGCUAUAAAAGUGUGGAUGAGUACAAGGUGCACAAAGGAAGUUAUAAUGGAUUUAACCAGUGUUUGACAACUACCCAGAGCAAAAUAUUUCAGUGUGAUAAAUAUGUGAAAGACUUUCAUAAAUUUUCAAAUUCAAAUAGACAUAAGACUGAAAAGAAUCCUUUCAAAUGUAAAGAAUGUGGCAAGUCAUUUUGUGUUCUUUCACACCUAACUCAACAUAAAAGAAUUCACACUACUGUCAAUUCCUACAAACUUGAAGAAUGUGGCAAGGCCUUUAAUGUGUCCUCAACCCUUUCUCAACAUAAGAGAAUUCAUACAGGACAAAAACACUACAAAUGUGAAGAAUGUGGCAUAGCCUUUAACAAGUCCUCACACCUUAACACACAUAAGAUAAUUCAUACUGGAGAGAAAUCCUACAAACGUGAAGAAUGUGGAAAAGCUUUUAACAUAUCCUCACACCUUACUACACAUAAGAUAAUUCAUACUGGAGAGAAUGCCUACAAAUGUAAAGAAUGUGGCAAAGCUUUUAACCAAUCAUCAACCCUUACUAGACAUAAGAUAAUUCAUGCUGGAGAGAAGCCCUACAUAUGUGAACAUUGUGGCAGAGCUUUUAACCAAUCCUCGAACCUUACUAAACAUAAGAGAAUUCAUACUGGUGAUAAACCUUAUAAAUGUGAAGAAUGUGGCAAAGCCUUUAAUGUGUCCUCAACCCUUACUCAACAUAAGAGAAUUCAUACUGGAGAGAAACCUUACAAAUGUGAAGAGUGUGGCAAAGCCUUUAACGUGUCCUCAACUCUUACUCAACAUAAGAGAAUUCAUACUGGAGAAAAACCAUACAAAUGUGAAGAAUGUGGCAAAGCCUUUAACACAUCCUCACACCUCACCACACAUAAAAGAAUUCAUACCGGAGAGAAACCCUACAAAUGUGAAGAAUGUGGCAAAGCCUUUAACCAGUUCUCACAACUUACUACACAUAAGAUAAUUCAUACUGGAGAGAAACCCUACAAAUGUAAAGAAUGUGGCAAAGCUUUUAAGCGGUCCUCAAACCUUACUGAACAUAGGAUAAUUCAUACUGGAGAGAAACCCUACAAAUGUGAAGAAUGUGGCAAAGCUUUUAACCUAUCCUCACACCUUACAACACAUAAGAAAAUUCAUACUGGAGAGAAACCCUACAAAUGUAAAGAAUGUGGCAAAGCUUUUAACCAAUCCUCGACACUUGCUAGACAUAAGAUAAUUCAUGCUGGAGAGAAACCCUACAAAUGUGAAGAAUGUGGCAAAGCUUUUUACCAAUACUCAAACCUUACUCAACAUAAGAUAAUUCAUACUGGAGAGAAACCCUACAAAUGUGAAGAAUGUGGCAAAGCCUUUAAUUGGUCCUCAACUCUGACUAAACAUAAGGUAAUUCAUACUGGAGAGAAACCCUACAAAUGUAAAGAAUGUGGCAAAGCUUUUAACCAAUGCUCAAACCUUACUACACACAAGAAAAUUCAUGCUGUAGAAAAAUCUGACAAAUAAGAAAAAUGGACCAGGCGUGGUGGCUCACACCUGUAAUCCCAGCACUUUGGGAGGCCAAGGCGGGUGGAUCACAAGAUCAAGAGAUUGAGACCAUCCUGGCCAACGAAGAGAAUUACUGGAGAGAAACCGUACAAACCUGAAAGAUAUAACAGUGCAGUUGACAACACCUCAAUAUUUCUAAACACCUUUAAAUGGUUGUCAUACUUGAUUGUAGGUAAAAUAUAGUAGAGGAAACCUCUACAAGUGUGAAGAAUGUGGCAAAACUUUUAACCAAUGCUGACACUUUAUUGGACAGGAAAUGAUGUAUACUUGAGAAAAAUUAUGCAAAUGUAAAGAAUGUGAAGAAGCCAUUAAUAUCUGUUCACAUCUUAUUCAAUAUCAGAGAGUUCAUACUUAAUAGAAGCAUUAAAGAUGAAAUUACUGUCAAUAGAUUUUUCAGAAAAUAUAAGCCUUUAAAGUGAAGAAGAGUAUUUAUUUUGAAGACAAGCAUUAAAAUAUCAAGAGUGUAAGCUGGGCAUGGUGGCUCAGGCCUGUAAUUUCAGCACUUUGGAGGCCAAGGCAGGUGGUUUACUUGAGGUCAGAAGUUCAAGACCAGCCUGGCCAACAUGGUGAAACUCCAUCUCUACCCAAAAUACAAAAAUUAGGUGGGUGUGGUAGUGCAUGACUAAUCCCAGCUACUCGGUGGUUGAGACAGGAGAAUCGCUUGAACCUGGGAGGCAGAGGUUGCAGUGAGCUGAGUUUGUGCCACCACACUCCAGCCUGGGCACUCCAGCUGCACUCCAUCUC